GCUGCUGAUGCUGAAGCUGUGCACCGAGGUCCGUGUGGCCAACGAGCUCAACGCCAGGCGCCGCUCCUUUACAGCCAUCUAUCUGCUGGGACCUCCACCCAGGCUCUGCUGGGACACCCACCAAGGCCUCCUCAUGAGACCUGGGCUUCCUCACAACAUGGCGGCCAGGUCCCAAGGGGGAGCUACCUGAGAAAGCAGGUGGAAGCUGUAUCUUUUUUAUGACCUAAGUCUUGGAAAUCACAGCAUUGCUUCUGUGGACUGGAGUGGUCACAAGCCCACCCAUGAUCAAGGGGAGAAGACACUGACACCACCUCCUGAUGCCGAGUGUGGAGGAAAAGGAAAAUGUUGCUGGGCCCUUUUUGGAUCCUGAGUGCCUGGUCUGGAGGACGUGUUCAGCACAGAUCUGUGGAAGUGUGUGACUGUUGAAAAUGUUCCUGGCAGCUCUCUCAGCAUCAGAACUCUGCAUUCCAUCCUACACAAACGUGGAUCUGAUCACACUGCUUUCCAGGCAAGGAGCCUCAGCUGCAGAUAGCAAGGAUGAAGAAGUCAAGGUUGCCCCCAGGCGGUCCUUCCUGGACUUCGACCCCCACCACUUCUGGCAGUGGAGCAGCUUCUCGGACUACGUGCAGUGCGUCCUGGCCUUCACGGGCGUGGCGGGCUACAUCACCUACCUGUCCAUUGACUCCGCCCUGUUUGUGGAGACCCUGGGCUUCCUGGCUGUGCUGACCGAAGCCAUGCUGGGUGUGCCCCAGCUUUACCGCAACCACCGCCACCAGUCCACGGAGGGCAUGAGCAUCAAGAUGGUGCUCAUGUGGACCAGUGGUGACGCCUUCAAGACGGCCUACUUCCUGCUGAAGGGUGCCCCUCUGCAGUUCUCCGUGUGCGGCCUGCUGCAGGUGCUGGUGGACCUGGCCAUCCUGGGGCAGGCCUACGCCUUCGCCCGCCACCCCCAGAAGCCGGCGCCCCACGCCGUGCACCCCACUGGCACCAAGGCCCUCUGACAGUGGGGAGGACGAGGAUGUGGGACCGCCAGCCGCGGGCACUGGUGGGCCCUGACCUCCCCGCGGGGAGGGUGGGUGCUGUGGCCCCUGCAGGUGUGGCAGAGAUGGGGCAUGGGCAUUGGGGUCUCCAUCAGCCUCUGUGGGGUGUCUCAGGGUGGGCAGUGGGGGUGGGGCUGGGACGCUGUUUGUGCUCAGCGGGGACAGCCAGGGUUGAUCUGGCCCCGAGGGUUUUGGAUGUUUUUAGGAUGACAUAAAAAGCAAGUGUUUUCCCCAUUUCCUCUUAUGAAACACCGUCUGAGCCCAAGGUACACAUUGGGCGGCCUGCAGGAACCUGCUCCAGGUGGACACACGGGCCAGCAGCCGCGAACCUUGAAGCUGGGGUGACCGCAGGAGACCCUGUAAGGCCUGUGAGCGGAGCCCUCGACCCCGUGACACCCUGGCCAGACACCCUGCUUGGACUGGGGUGGCCUCUGCUACCCAGGGGUCUGGCACGGGGGAGGGCUGGGGCUUUCUCUGCCUGGUACACACGGAAAGGCGGCUGUGCGGACGCAGGGUCACCGUGCUCCGGGUUUUCUGACAGUCGGUGUUUCCUGGGCCUUUGGAGUGGCUGCGAGGCCUGAACGCCUUGUGGAUCCGCUGUGUCCAGCCCGGCUGAGCAUCGCCAGGGCUAGCUCAUGCUGCUCUUGUCAGCCUCUGGUUCUCCUCGAGUCCUUGGGGACGUGGCAGAUGCCAGCGACCAUCAGACAACGUGGAGGCCCUCAUGGGCAAUGGCUGAGGGGGCCGGGCUGAGGCUGUGCACAUGCAGUCUGCACGCCACUCUUGGGCUCUGCUGGCGGAGAUCCCCUUCCUUCUGGGUGCAGACUGCACCUCCGGAUGCAGUUUUGAUGUCCAUCUUCCAGGAGAGACGGUCUCGGGUCCAGGGAGUGGAGGGGGCUGCCCCUGCCGUGCAGGUCCUGGCCGAUGGCGCCUUACCCUGCUGCCCUGGGCUUUUGGCCUGAAGCAAAUUCCUGAGUGGGGGGUACUGGGGCCUGCCGCAUCCUGUCCUGUCCACUGCCCACCCCCGUGUGCUGGCUCCCUCACUUCUGGCUGCAGUGGGAGCCGCCAGUCUGACCCUUGUCACCGCACGCUCUGCCCCCACCCCGUUGCAAGAGGUCACACCAUGUCAGCAGCCUUGCACUGACCGCAGCCGGCCCCCAGGCCUCAGAGUUCUGGAUGCUUCCGUGCGGCUCCAACAGGCAUCGUCUUCCCUUCCGCAGGUGGAGGGGCCGCUUCCCGCAGGCAUCUGAGCUCUGUGCCGGGGCCGUGGCCAUGGGAAGAUGUUCCACGCUGCCUCCUCCUCGAGUUUUCCUCGGAAACACUCUUGAAUGUCUGAGUGAGGGUCCUGCUUAGCUCUUUGGCCUGUGAGAUGCUUUGAAAAUUUUUAUUUUUUUAAGAUGAAGCAAGAUGUCUGUAGCGGUAAUUGCCUCACAUUAAACUGUCGCCGACUGCAGGCGCAGUGACUGCUGAAUGUACCCUGUGUGGCGACUUGGAAUCAAUAAACCAUUUGUGGAUCCUGA